CCCCUCUCCCAGAGUGGGCGGCCCCUCCCCUUUCUCUGAGUGGGCGGGGACAGCGGUUGCAUGGGCAGCUUUCCUUAUGAUGCCACAGGUCCCUCUGGACAUGCUGCUGCCUGGCCACGCCUCCUUUCCCUUUCAUCUUUCUCACUGACCAAUGGGCUUGGAGCCUUAAGGCCACGCCCCUAUUCUGCGUUCCAUUGGUGCCCUGGUUACGCCACCUGUGGCUCAGUUGCACAGCUGCCUGGUAGGUGACUGGAGGCAUUGAGCAGUGCUCACUGGUAUUUCGCUGAUGUGGCCCCAACCCCGCCUCCCUCCCCACCCUGCGAUGUCAGAAAAAACACAACAGGGGAAAUUGGCCGCAGCCAAGAAAAAGUUAAAAGCAUAUUGGCAGAGGAAGAGCCCUGGCAUUCCAGCAGGAGCUAACAGGAAAAAGAAAGUCAAUGGCAGUAGCCCUGACACAGCCACUUCUGGUGGUUACCACUCACCUGGGGAUUCAGCAACAGGUAUCUACGGGGAGGGCCGUGCAUCCUCUACUACCCUGCAGGAUCUGGAGAGCCAGUACCAAGAACUAGCAGUGGCCCUGGAUUCAAGCUCCGCAAUAAUCAGUCAACUCACUGAAAACAUCAAUUCACUGGUUCGCACAUCUAAGGAGGAGAAGAAGCAUGAGAUACAUCUGGUACAGAAGCUUGGGAGGAGCUUGUUCAAACUCAAAAACCAGACGGCUGAACCCCUGGCCCCAGAGCCCCCAGCAGGGCCAUCUAAGGUGGAGCAGCUACAAGAUGAGACCAACCACCUAAGGAAGGAGCUAGAGAGUGUGGGAAGACAGCUCCAGGCUGAGGUGGAAAACAAUCAGAUGUUGAGUCUCCUGAACAGGAGACAGGAGGAGAGGCUACGUGAACAGGAGGAGAGGCUACAUGAACAGGAGGGGAGGCUACAUGAACAGGAGGAGAGGCUGUGUGAACAGGAGGAGAGGCUACGUGAACAGGAGGAGAGGCUGUGUGAACAGGAGGAGAGGCUACGUGAACAGGAGGAGAGGCUGUGUGAACAGGAGGAGAGGCUACAUGAACAGGAGGAGAGGCUGUGUGAACAGGAGGAGAGGCUAUGUGAACAGGAGGAGAGGCUGUGUGAACAGGAGAAGCUGCCAGGGCAGGAGAGGCUGCUGGAAGAGGUGGAGAAGCUGUUAGAACAGGAGAGGCGGCAGGAGGAGCAGGAGAGGCUGCUGGAGAGGGAGAGGCUGCUGGACGAGGUGGAGGAGCUCCUGGAGCAGGAGAGGCUUCGGCAACAGGAUGAGAGGCUGUGGCAGCAGGAGACUCUGCGGGAGCUGGAGAGGCUGCGGGAGCUGGAGAGGCUGCGGGAGCUGGAGAGGAUGCUGGAGCUGGGGUGGGAAGCCCUGUACGAGCAGCGGGCCGAGCCACGCAGCGGCUUCGAGGAGCUGAACAACGAGAACAAGAGCACACUGCAGUUGGAGCAGCAAGUAAAGGAGCUGGAGAAGUCGGGUGGAGCUGAAGAGCCAAGAGGCUCCGAGUCUGCAGCAGCAGCCAGACCAGUACCUGGAGCCCCAGUCCCACAAGGAGCUUGGAUGUGCGGACAAGCAGGGUGGACUCCCCAGGAGCACCCAGGCUUGAGUGGAGAAGCUGUUGGUACAGGAGAGGCGGCAGGAGGAGCAGAAGAGGCUGCAUGCCAUUCUUUUCGGGCUGCGGAGAACAGGGAGCUAAACAUCACCAUCAUCUAAGAGCGGGUCAAGAAAUUGAAAAAAAAAAAAAAAACAAAACAUUUAAGGGGUUAAUAUCCUACACAAUUCAUUUACUUCAUUUGAAUGUUAGAGCCACUUAUGUUUAUUUGUGUUUCUAAUUUAUAGUUUAAAUUUAUUUGUGUUUCUAAUUUAUAAUUUAAAUUUAUUUGUGUUUCUAAUUUAUAGUUUAAAUUUAUUUGUGUUUCUAAUUUAUAAUUUAAAUUUAUUUGUAAAAAGUUAAAUGAGAGUGGGUCUUUCUCUCAUGUUCACUCUGGCAUCUUUUAGCAUUUUUUUAAUUUGAUAAUUAUAGGACGUUAGCAUGCAUAUCGAGUUUGCCCUUAUGUGGUGGGAGUUCAAACACACAAAGACCCACUGUAUGCACACAACUGUUCUUGCUGGUUUGGGAUAGGCUGCCAUGCUUUUUUAAUGUUAGUACAGCCUGUAUAUUCAUUACGGAAUUCAGAUAAAAUUUCCUUAUGUUCUGCUGUUAUGUUUGAUCGAAUCCUAAUCACAGUGAGCUCUUCAUUAGCUCAAUAUGUGGUUUGCCCUCAAGUGCGCGGUCUAUUACUUUGUAAUAUGCCACUGUGAGUACUGACAUUUACAGUUGUUUAAAGGUGGAGCACUGGAAACAGCCUUUCCCCCUUUUUCUGUGUAUUGGGGAUGGGAGUAAUAACAUUUUGGGGAGGUUUUUAAAUCUCCCAGAAGAGGAAAGUGGCCUGCUUUGGCAGGUGUGUGCAGGAUAGAAUAUGUUUCAUUUGUUCCGGUGCCAAGAAUGAGCGCUGUACUACGGUAGUUCCCUUAGGAUUUGUAUGUGCUCUGGGCUCAUGAAGAUACUGCCUCAUGAGCUGUGGCAGUUGUACUCUUUUUUGAUGACCUGAAAAGGGAUUAUUUCUGAGGAAUGAAAGGCUCCCAUCAUGACUGUGGAUGUGGAAAACCUUUUCUAGCUGAGAGCAUUUAUAUCUACAAUACAUUUUAAAGUCAGAGUUCAUGUUCCCUGUUUUAAUCACAUGACUACAUGUCCCAGUACACAAAAGGGCACUGGUUGGCGUUCUCCUUAAUGUAUUUAGUAAAGAUCAGAAGAAAUCCUUUAAGAGUUUAAAUGCCCCUGGAACAGGCAUAUACAGGCUCUAGUCAAGAAUGAAUUCGAGUGAAGGAAAGCUGUGUGACACCUGGCAUUCCUCUGUGUUCAUGGAGCUUAUUUGAGGCUAGAAGAUGGAUUUUACCAUCUAGACCUCUCUGGCUAAUAGCUAGUCUUCAACCAUCUGACAUAGGAAUUUACUUCUUUUCCUUGAAUGGAGAACACUUUAAAAAUAAUAACAAACAUUAUUAUAAACUAAUAUAUGUGAGAGUACUUAGUUGAAACAAAAAGGAGUUUUAGUAGACAGUAUUAUACUACAUUUGAAAAUCAAGGAGCAGUUUAUGCAACGUAAAAUGUUUACAAACUGCAGCGCAAUCUACUGUUUGUGACUGUCAAAGUGUCAUGAGGAAAGUGUCUAUACAAUCACAGAGUUAUAUUUCCUCACAAAGUUCUUUACGAAGAGUGAAAUAUGUUUUUAUACCUCUCAGUUUCAGUUAGAGGCAUAUUUUGUGUAAUAUUUAUGGCUUAAAAUGGACUAAAGGUCCUGUUCUUGCCUUGUCUGAACUUGCCGCUUUUGCAUUCUUUGAGUUCAGUUUAAAGACACUUACUUUAACUCCAUUUUAAACCCUCGGGCUAGAAAUCGUACCACUGUUAAUUAGCCACGUUAUUUGGUCUAACAGUUUUUGUUUAUCAUUCUGAAACUGAGCUUAUCUAAUACAUUGAUAAAUUAUUUCAAAGGUAUUUUUAUAGUUCAAAUCGCUUCACUUUUACCCUGACACGUAUAAAUGACUAGGAAUGACCUUCAGAUAGCGUUUAGCAACUGUAACCAAUCUGACAAUAAUGUGUUCAUCAGGUACCUGUGGAUUAAAUCACAUACUGGCAUAUUUAAGAUGAAUGUCAGUCUGAAAAAUAAAUAUACUAUAUUAAUUCAAAUACGACUCUUUGUGUAGGUAUUUUGUCAUAUGUUUAAGAAAAAGCUAAAGAGAAUGGAAAUCCUAUGACAAUAACUCAAGUCUUUCUUCAAAGUGCAUGCAGUCUUUUGCAGUACCUCAUUCAGCCAAGUAUUUGUUCUCUACCUCAUUCAGUAUAAGGCAGCCUUUAAUUUGCUUAGAAGGCAACAUUAGAAGGUUAGAGUUCAGCAGGAACAUAGAAUUUUAAAAUGUGACUUCAACUGAAUAAAUUUGAAUUUCUGUAGGGAGUAAAGAAUCAAAACACCUAUUUAAAGACUGCAAAAUAUGAUAAUUAUUUUUAAAGUAAUUGAUUAAACCUGGUAGGUUUUCCCAAAAUGAAAAACAAUCAGUUCUAAAACCAAAGCUGAUUUUUAGAAAAUGUGAAAAUGUAAAUCAACCCUAUCCAUAAUAGAUUCUCUAAAACUUUAUCUUACAGUCACUUUCAAAUAACUAUUCAAAAAUGUAACUGCUAUAUUAACGUCUUAAAAUAAUUUAAAACAUUUUAAAAUAUGAAUACUGUAGUUUAAAACAAAGAAUCUAGGGGAAGGAAAAGUAGACAAAGAAAUGCCAAUUCCAGUCCAAAGCUGUAUUUGCCAAGUUUUCUUAGAAUGACUUUUACCGAUUUAUGAAUUCUUAUACACAGAAUGCAUAAUGGAAAUACUGAUUUUUGUCUAAAGUGGCAUUAUUGACUGCUGCUGUGAUGCUACUGUAAUGUAAUACAUUAUUAAAUUGUUUCAAGGUGC